AGACGCCGAGGCGAGGGAUGCGCGCGGCGGGCGGUGGCUCCGAGCGGCGGCCGGGCGGGGGGCGCUGGAGGCCAGGCCGGCCAGCGGGGGGUAUCCCGAGAGCUCCAUGAAGUCCCCCCGGGGCCGCGGACGGGGCGCUGGCUUGGGGAGGCUGUCGGGGGGGCCCCGACAUCCAUGGCAAGGCGGGGGCCGCGGCGGCGCGCUCGGAGGCCGGCGGCGGCGGCUGCCCCGAGGGACGCGGCCCUAGGCGGUGGCGAUGGGGACCGCCCGGAUCGCACCCGGCCUGGCGCUCCUGCUCUGCUGCCCCGUGCUCAGCUCCGCGUACGCGCUGGUGGAUGCAGAUGACGUCAUGACUAAAGAGGAACAGAUCUUCCUGCUGCACCGUGCUCAGGCCCAGUGCGAAAAACGGCUCAAGGAGGUCCUGCAGAGGCCAGCACAGCUGACAGCCAUCAUUACCACCCUGGUUUCUCCAGCCAGCAUAAUGGAAUCAGACAAGGGAUGGACAUCUGCGUCCACAUCAGGGAAGCCCAGGAAAGAUAAGGCAUCUGGGAAGCUCUACCCUGAGUCUGAGGAGGACAAGGAGGCACCCACUGGCAGCAGGUACCGAGGGCGCCCCUGUCUGCCGGAAUGGGACCACAUCCUGUGCUGGCCGCUGGGGGCACCAGGUGAGGUGGUGGCUGUGCCCUGUCCGGACUACAUUUAUGACUUCAAUCACAAAGGCCAUGCCUACCGACGCUGUGACCGCAAUGGCAGCUGGGAGCUGGUGCCUGGGCACAACAGGACGUGGGCCAACUACAGCGAGUGUGUCAAAUUUCUCACCAAUGAGACUCGUGAACGGGAGGUGUUUGACCGCCUGGGCAUGAUUUACACCGUGGGCUACUCCGUGUCCCUGGCGUCCCUCACCGUAGCUGUGCUCAUCCUGGCCUACUUUAGGCGGCUGCACUGCACGCGCAACUACAUCCACAUGCACCUGUUCCUGUCCUUCAUGCUGCGCGCCGUGAGCAUCUUCGUCAAGGACGCUGUGCUCUACUCUGGCGCCACGCUUGAUGAGGCUGAGCGCCUCACCGAGGAGGAGCUGCGCGCCAUCGCCCAGGCGCCCCCGCCGCCUGCCACCGCCGCUGCCGGCUACGCGGGCUGCAGGGUGGCUGUGACCUUCUUCCUUUACUUCCUGGCCACCAACUACUACUGGAUUCUGGUGGAGGGGCUGUACCUGCACAGCCUCAUCUUCAUGGCCUUCUUCUCAGAGAAGAAGUACCUGUGGGGCUUCACAGUCUUCGGCUGGGGUCUGCCCGCUGUCUUCGUGGCUGUGUGGGUCAGUGUCAGAGCUACCCUGGCCAACACCGGGUGCUGGGACUUGAGCUCCGGGAACAAAAAGUGGAUCAUCCAGGUGCCCAUCCUGGCCUCCAUUGUGCUCAACUUCAUCCUCUUCAUCAAUAUCGUCCGGGUGCUCGCCACCAAGCUGCGGGAGACCAACGCCGGCCGGUGUGACACACGGCAGCAGUACCGGAAGCUGCUCAAAUCCACGCUGGUGCUCAUGCCCCUCUUUGGCGUCCACUACAUUGUCUUCAUGGCCACACCAUACACCGAGGUCUCAGGGACGCUCUGGCAAGUCCAGAUGCACUAUGAGAUGCUCUUCAACUCCUUCCAGGGAUUUUUUGUCGCAAUCAUAUACUGUUUCUGCAAUGGCGAGGUACAAGCUGAGAUCAAGAAAUCUUGGAGCCGCUGGACACUGGCACUGGACUUCAAGCGAAAGGCACGCAGCGGGAGCAGCAGCUAUAGCUACGGCCCCAUGGUGUCCCACACAAGUGUGACCAAUGUCGGCCCCCGUGUGGGACUCGGCCUGCCCCUCAGCCCCCGCCUACUGCCCACUGCCACCACCAACGGCCACCCUCAGCUGCCUGGCCAUGCCAAGCCAGGGACCCCAGCCCUGGAGACCCUCGAGACCACACCACCUGCCAUGGCUGCUCCCAAGGACGAUGGGUUCCUCAACGGCUCCUGCUCAGGCCUGGACGAGGAGGCCUCUGGGCCUGAGCGGCCACCUGCCCUGCUACAGGAAGAGUGGGAGACAGUCAUGUGACCAGGCGCUGGGGGCUGGACCUGCUGACAUAGUGGAUGGACAGAUGGACCAAAAGAUGGGUGGUUGAAUGAUUUCCCACUCAGGGCUGGGGCCAAGAGGAAAAACAGGGAAAAAAAGAAAAAAAAAAGAAAAAGGAAAAGGAA